GGAUUCAGCUGAUCAGGAGCAAGAUCAGCCAGUGUGCCUCUUUCAAAAAGCCCAGCCUACCUCUCUGAUGUAAAAUAAGUACAAAAAUGACGGUGCAAUUUAUGCAAAUGCUGUUUGCAGAAGGGUUCCGUUCGAGCGCUGUGUUUGCAGAAGGGUUCCGUUCGAGCGCUGUGUUUGCAGAAGGGUUCCGUUCGAGCCCUGUGUUUGCAGAAGGGUUCCGUUCGAGCCCUGUGUUUGCAGAAGGGUUCCAUUCGAGCGCUGUGUUUGCAGAAGGGUUCCGUUGGAGCGCUGUGUUUGCAGAAGGGUUCCGUUGGAGCCCUGUGUUUGCAGAAGGGUUCCGUUCGAGCCCUGUGUUUGCAGAAGGGUUCCGUUCGAGCCCUGUGUUUGCAGAAGGGUUCCGUUCGAGCGCUGUGUUUGCAGAAGGGUCCUGUUCAAGUGCUGGGAGCACAGUGCUUUCUUCCAGGGCCACCCUGUGCCAGGGGCCCUGGGCUCGUCACCUCCCUGGGAUGCUCCUUCAGCAGCAAGAGCACUGGCUGGGCCCCUCUGAACGCUCCUGUGAGGACGUUCCUUGGGGAAUCACUUGGAAGUGCUUUCAGCUCAGCCUCCAUAGCCCUGCGGACCUCAGUGAAGCGCAGGCAUAAGUGGUGAGAUGCCAACUGCAGACCUGACGUUUGGGGGCAAUUUACAAACACCUUGGAAAGGCGCCCUAGGAGAAAAGUAAAACUCAGAUAAAGGAGGGGGAAAAUAAAAAUAAAGGGCCAAAAUCUGACAAGUA